AGAGACAAGGCUGUGGGCUGGUCAGAAGCUGGUUACAAUUCCUCCCGCCCCAGUACUUGCUGGCAGGGAUUAAGAGCAGAUAAAAGUGUGCUCACACACUGUAGACACGGCUACCAUGCCAUCCACAGUGUUGCCAUCCACAGUGUUGCCAUCACUCCUGCCCACAGCAGGAGCUGGCUGGAGCAUGAGGUGGAUUCUGUGCUGGAGCCUCACCCUCUGCCUGAUGGCGCAGACGGCCUUGGGUGCCUUGCACACCAAGAGGCCUCAAGUGGUCACCAAAUAUGGAACCCUGCAAGGAAAACAGAUGCAUGUGGGGAAGACACCCAUCCAAGUCUUUUUAGGAGUCCCCUUCUCCAGACCUCCUCUAGGUAUCCUCAGGUUUGCACCUCCAGAACCCCCGGAGCCCUGGAAAGGAAUCAGAGAUGCUACCACCUACCCGCCUGGAUGGAGUCUCGCUCUGUCGCCAGGCUGGAGUGCAGUGGCACGAUCUCGGCUCACUGCAACCUCCGCCUCCCGGGUUCAAGCGAGUCUCCUGCCUCAGCCUCUGAGUAUCUGGGGCUACAGGUGCCUGCAGGAGUCCUGGGGCCAGCUGGCCUCGAUGUACGUCAGCACGCGGGAACGGUACAAGUGGCUGCGCUUCAGCGAGGACUGUCUGUACCUGAACGUGUACGCGCCGGCGCGCGCGCCCGGGGAUCCCCAGCUGCCAGUGAUGGUCUGGUUCCCGGGAGGCGCCUUCAUCGUGGGCGCUGCUUCUUCGUACGAGGGCUCUGACUUGGCCGCCCGCGAGAAAGUGGUGCUGGUGUUUCUGCAGCACAGGCUCGGCAUCUUCGGCUUCCUGAGGUGGCGGGGCCGCACGGACGACAGCCACGCGCGCGGGAACUGGGGGCUGCUGGACCAGAUGGCGGCUCUGCGCUGGGUGCAGGAGAACAUCGCAGCCUUCGGGGGAGACCCAGGAAAUGUGACCCUGUUCGGCCAGUCGGCGGGGGCCAUGAGCAUCUCAGGACUGAUGAUGUCACCCCUAGCCUCGGGUCUCUUCCAUCGGGCCAUUUCCCAGAGUGGCACCGCGUUAUUCAGACUUUUCAUCACUAGUAACCCACUGAAAGUGGCCAAGAAGGUUGCCCACCUGGCUGGAUGCAACCACAACAGCACACAGAUCCUGGUAAACUGCCUGAGGGCACUAUCAGGGACCAAGGUGAUGCGUGUGUCCAACAAGAUGAGAUUCCUCCAACUGAACUUCCAGAGAGACCCGGAAGAGAUUAUCUGGUCCAUGAGCCCUGUGGUGGAUGGUGUGGUGAUCCCAGAUGACCCUUUGGUGCUCCUGACCCAGGGGAAGGUUUCAUCUGUGCCCUACCUUCUAGGUGUCAACAACCUGGAAUUCAAUUGGCUCUUGCCUUAUAUCAUGAAGUUCCCGCUAAACCGGCAGGCGAUGAGAAAGGAAACCAUCACUAAGAUGCUCUGGAGUACCCGCACCCUGUUGAAUAUCACCAAGGAGCAGGUACCACUUGUGGUGGAGGAGUACCUGGACAAUGUCAAUGAGCAUGACUGGAAGAUGCUACGAAACCGUAUGAUGGACAUAGUUCAAGAUGCCACUUUCGUGUAUGCCACACUGCAGACUGCUCACUACCACCGAGAUGCCGGCCUCCCUGUCUACCUGUAUGAAUUUGAGCACCACGCUCGUGGAAUAAUCGUCAAACCCCGCACUGAUGGGGCAGACCAUGGGGAUGAGAUGUACUUCCUCUUUGGGGGCCCCUUCGCCACAGGCCUUUCCAUGGGUAAGGAGAAGGCACUUAGCCUCCAGAUGAUGAAAUACUGGGCCAACUUUGCCCGCACAGGAAACCCCAAUGAUGGGAAUCUGCCCUGCUGGCCACGCUACAACAAGGAUGAAAAGUACCUGCAGCUGGAUUUUACCACAAGAGUGGGCAUGAAGCUCAAGGAGAAGAAGAUGGCUUUUUGGAUGAGUCUGUACCAGUCUCAAAGACCUGAGAAGCAGAGGCAAUUCUAAGGGUGGCUAUGCAGGAAGGAGCCAAAGAGGGGUUUGCCCCCACCAUCCAGGCCCUGGGGAGACUAGCCAUGGACAUACCUGGGGACAAGAGUUCUACCCACCCCAGUUUAGAACUGCAGGAGCUCCCUGCUGCCUCCAGGCCAAAGCUAGAGCUUUUGCCUGUUGUGUGGGACCUGCACUGCCCUUUCCAGCCUGACAUCCCAUGAUGCCCCUCUACUUCACUGUUGACAUCCAGUUAGGCCAGGCCCUGUCAACACCACACUGUGCUCAGCUCUCCAGCCUCAGGACAACCUCUUUUUUUCCCUUCUUCAAAUCCUCCCACCCUUCAAUGUCUCCUUGUGACUCCUUCUUAUGGGAGGUCGACCCAGACUGCCACUGCCCCUGUCACUGCACCCAGCUUGGCAUUUACCAUCCAUCCUGCUCAACCUUGUGCCUGUCUGUUCACAUUGGCCUGGAGGCCUAGGGCAGGUUGUGACAUGGAGCAAACUUUUGGUAGUUUGGGAUCUUCUCUCCCACCCACACUUAUCUCCCCCAGGGCCACUCCAAAGUCUAUACACAGGGGUGGUCUCUUCAAUAAAGAAGUGUUGAUUAGACCUGAAUUUCUCCACCUAUAAAAUGGGUGUGUGAAGUGAAUGAUGUCUCAAUUUGAGCCCUGAGAGAAAGGAAGUAUUGCUGCCUGUUCCUUAGUGGGCUGUGCCUGGAUGCUACACUCAGUCAAAGGGUGCUACUGCAAAGUUGCCUGGGGUACAAAACACUUGCCUUUUGCCUUCAUGGUCUCAAGUGCACCCCUCAGGACAGCCACACCCCACGCUCACUUGUCCAUCAGUUUAGGUCUUAGUGCCACAUCUAGAUUCCUCUGGCCUCUCCUGCAGCCCGUGUGUAUCCCAGCCUGUCCCACAGUUUUGUUUCGUUGUUUUGUGGGGUUUUUUUUUUUUUUUUUGAGACGGAGUUUUGCUCUUGUCACCCAGGCUGGAGUGCAAUGAUGAAAUCUCAGCUCACUGCAGCCUCAGUCUCCCGAGUUCAAGCGAUUCUCCUGCCUCAGCCUCCCAAGUAGCUGAGAUUACAGAUGCCCACCACCAUGCCCGGCUUAUUUUUGUAUUUUUAGUAGAGAUAGGGUUUCAUCAUGUCAGCCAGGCUGGUCUCAAACUCCUGACCUCAGGUAAUCCACCCGUCUCAGCCUGCUGAAGUGCUGGAAUUACAGGCAUGAGCCACCAUGCCUGGCCACUGUGGGCUUUUUGGUGGUAAAAUACACACGACAAAUUUUACCAUUUUAAC